GAGAGGGUGCGCGAUGGCGCCAGCUGGAGUGCGGCUGGCGGAGGAAGGAGCCUGGCGGCGGGUUGGGGGCUGGGUAACUGGGGCUGGGGGUUUGUCAAGGGGUUGGCGCGUAGUGAUGACGCAAAGGCUUUGUACCUGGGGCUUCGCAGUGGGACGGAAAUUGGGAGUGGAGGGCGGUGGCCUAGAUCCUCACCUCUUCGUAUUGUUUCACGCGGCAGUGCUUGGGAGUCAGUGUAGCUCCAGUCAGUGUUAUCAGCACCUUCGCACUGGCGCUUUGCCAGGGAAGAGAGUUAUCUAUGGCUUGAAUACCUCGGUGCCGUCCUCUCGUUUCUCUGGGAAACUGCAGUACGGAGAUGCUUUCUCCAGUAAUGAGAAGGCCUUUGGUGUCUCUUCGGGGCUUCUGGGACUGCAGUAGAGAGAGAGGUGGAGGAAAACAAUAAGGAUUUGAAAUUUCCCUGCCCAAGAAUCAACAGGAACUCUGUUUAUAGACCAGAAAUGUGACAUCUAUCUUUGGUACAUAAAUAAAGGAUAAAAUAUUUUAUGAAACAAAUCUUCAAUCAAGUAUAACAUUUUGAUGCUUGGCAUCUAGACUCCCUUGUGCCCUCACUAUGCCAGCGGCAACUGUAGAUCAUAGCCAAAGAAUUUGUGAAGUUUGGGCUUGCAACUUGGAUGAAGAGAUGAAGAAAAUUCGUCAAGUUAUCCGAAAAUAUAAUUACGUUGCUAUGGACACCGAGUUUCCAGGUGUGGUUGCAAGACCCAUUGGAGAAUUCAGGAGCAAUGCUGACUAUCAAUACCAACUAUUGCGGUGUAAUGUAGACUUGUUAAAGAUAAUUCAGCUAGGACUGACAUUUAUGAAUGAGCAAGGAGAAUACCCUCCAGGAACUUCAACUUGGCAGUUUAAUUUUAAAUUUAAUUUGACGGAGGACAUGUAUGCCCAGGACUCUAUAGAGCUACUAACAACAUCUGGUAUCCAGUUUAAAAAACAUGAGGAGGAAGGAAUUGAAACCCAGUACUUUGCAGAACUUCUUAUGACUUCUGGAGUGGUCCUCUGUGAAGGGGUCAAAUGGUUGUCAUUUCAUAGCGGUUACGACUUUGGCUACUUAAUCAAAAUCCUAACCAACUCUAACUUGCCUGAAGAAGAACUUGACUUCUUUGAGAUCCUUCGAUUGUUUUUUCCUGUCAUUUAUGAUGUGAAGUACCUCAUGAAGAGCUGCAAAAAUCUCAAAGGUGGAUUACAGGAGGUGGCAGAACAGUUAGAGCUGGAACGGAUAGGACCACAACAUCAGGCAGGAUCUGAUUCAUUGCUCACAGGAAUGGCCUUUUUCAAAAUGAGAGAAAUGUUCUUUGAAGAUCAUAUUGAUGAUGCCAAAUAUUGUGGUCAUUUGUAUGGCCUUGGUUCUGGUUCAUCCUAUGUACAGAAUGGCACAGGGAAUGCAUAUGAAGAGGAAGCCAACAAGCAGUCAUGACAUGAAAUAGUCCUUUUAUUUUUAUUUCGAGCUACACACAUGCUUGUAUAUAGGUUUUAUCUCUGGUUGAAUCCCUCGAACAAUAGACAGUACCUUUCCCCCCCCUUUCAUGGCCCAUUUUAUUGUCUGCCUUUCAGUACUAAGUAUGACCGUUCCUAUCUCAGAUCUUAAUAAAAAGAAAAAAAAAAACGCAUUCAGGUUAAAUUUGGCCUUAAUUUAAUAUACUUGUUAGCAAGCGUGUGUGACAGAGAGUGGGGAAAGCUACAUCAUUGAAUAUUUUGAUAAACUUUACCGACUUGAGUUUGGUUUAUUUUUCCCUUUUCCUAAAUUAACUAGCACUGACUGUAAUUUAUUUCCCUGUUUCACGUCUCUCCCUUCCAUUCUGCAGGAGUUUUAGCUAUUUGAGAUCGUGGACCAUCAGUUUUGCACUUUAGAGAGUGUUUCUGACUCUAAACCUGUUUUAUCAGAAAAUUUGUUUUUUCUUGAUCUUAGCUGGAAAAAUCUGCCAACUUUACACAGUAUUUACUUGGUUUUGACCCACAGAAUAUAGCACGUUGUGCAAACUGUCGAUUCAGCGAAACUUAAAAAAGACAAGAAACUACUGAGGAGCUUAGUAACUGCUGUUUCUGUACGUAGUGUUUAAUCUUCCAAGCACAUCUAGUGUCUGUCAGUUUCUAAUUGGCAUGUGUAGGCUGCUCUGUGACUGAAGAAUUUUCAAACCAGCUUUACACCCUUCAGGAAAAAUCCCUUGUGAUUGGAUGUUUACUAUCUGCCAGGAAACUGGUACUCAAGAUGUUGAAGCUACAGUUAUUUUAUGAUAGCACACUUCCCUUGAUCUGCUUAUUUUUAUUCCAUCACCAUUUACCCUUUUUUUUUUUUUAAAUUUUGUAGCCAUUCUUAUGAUGCUCUUGAUUUGUUGGUUACACAAAUCAAUUUUAUUAAAAAUCCAAAGAUAAGUCUUUAGGUAUAUUUUGUACCAAAUUAAAUUAGAAGACAAAAAUUGUGCUUUCAUAGUUGCUACAAAGGUAAAUAAUGGAGAGAUUUGGUACAAAACAACAAAAUAUAUAUAUAUUCUCAUAUAUAUAUAUAUAGCUGAUAAAAUUACCUGAGGAGUGUAAUGCUUAUUUUUUUGUGUAUAUCUUUGCAAUCUAUUUUAUAUAUAUUGACAAAAGAGACUGUGAAAUACUUAGCCAUGCAGAAUAUGUGACCAGACCAGAGCAUGUGUAGGAAGACUUUACGGUAAUCAUUAACUCUACCCCGAAAUGAUGGACUACAAGUUAUAAUGUGUGUUACCUACACUUCAAUCAGUAAUAUUAGCAAAUCUCCAAAUGUUAGUCACAUUGGUUUGUCUCCCUUGUACAUUCUUUAUUCAUGAUAUUACAGUGCUGUAACUGGGUGGUCCUUUUUAAACAAAACAUUAUUUGCAAAACAGAGGGUAUUAUUUGUUUUUAAAGCUUUUGUAAAUAAAGGCUUCAAAAUGUUUUCUUAUAAAUGUUGAUGACUGGUGAUUUUCUUUUGGAAAUACUUAUUUGGGGGAUAUUGUUCAUUUUUAUUUGGGCAACUCAACAGAAUUCAGUAACUUCCUUCAUUAACCCUAGAUGAUUAUUAGUCCAUUAAUUGAAAAAUCAGUCUGAGUUUUCUGCAUUUCAAGUGUUGGCUUAUUCUUGUUCUUUAUGAGUACCUCAACUAGCUAAUUAAGGACUGACUUCUGUUUCUCCUUUCCAGGAAUGCAUUUAUUCCGAAGGAUAUACUUCACAAAGUAAAUACAUUUGGUAUAACUGUGGCUUUUUAAAAAAUCUAACACAAUGUAGUAAGUUUCUAACUGGCUUCUUUUGUCUUCGUUAAAAAGGAAGUGAAGCUUCUUUUCGCUUGUGAUUUGUUAGCUGAGAAAACUAAUAUUUAAAUUCUGUUCAACUAUUUGAGAAAUCAAUGCUGGAUUUCAAAUAGGAAUGAUAAAGAUUGCCUUUUUAUUAGCCACAUAGUUGCUCAAUCUCAUAACUUGUAUCAUUUCUGGCUUCUGUCCCUAAAAAGUAUAGAUAAUCCCUAACUUACUUUCGACUUAAUGAUUUUUCAACUUUACAGUGGGUGUAUUGAGAGGUAACCCCAUCAAAAGUUUAGGAGCGCCUUAGGACCAAAGAUGGGGUUAUAGUUUCUACUGAAUGUGUAUUGCUUUUGCACCAUUGCAAAGUCAAAAUUUAUAACUUGAACCAUCGUAAAUUGGGGGACUGUAUGCUGUUGCCUGCAUUAAAUGCAUCUUAGUAUUUUUUCAGAUGUAACCUCAUUGUAGGUUGAGCAACCGUAUAGUGUAACUUUUGUAGAGGAACAUUUUGACUUUUACUGGGUCUAAGUUUUACUUUUUUAUUUUGUUCCAGACAGUCUCAAUGUUUGUAAAGUCUAGGUUCCAGAUGUAAGAUAUUUGGCUGAUAUUUUAGUGUUACUGAGCCAUUAAUUAAUUACAGGCUCAUAUAUUCUGUUAAAUCUACUAGAGCAAGGGUUGUCAAACUAUGGCCCGUAGCCAGAAUCAGCUUGCUGCCUGUUUUUGUGUGGCCCAUGAACUGAAAAUGGCUUUUAAAUGGUUGGGAAAAAUAAUCAAAAGAUUAUUUCCUGACAUCUGAAAAUUACAUGAAAUUCAAAUUUUAGUGUCUAUAAGUUUUUAUUGGAAUGCAGCCACACUAAUUUACAUAUUAUCUAUGGAUACUUUUUUGCUAUAAUGGGAAAGUUGAGUAGCUGCUACAGAACCUGUGUAUGUGUGUCUUGUUUCACAUUGCCGCUUGGCAAGCUACAGAAUCAUGGUGAUGCAGAUAUUACCUGAAAGCAUUUGGAAUGCCCUGUGUAUUGCUAGAUUUAUUACUUUUUCUGCUACCAGUUCAUGCCCUGUAUCUCAGAACAAGAAAAGUACCUUUGAAUGUUACACUUUCAAGGCACAUUGGAAUAUGGACUAUUUUAUUAUAUGCUGGUACAUUGUGUUUAUAAUGCAGUGUCACCAUAACUGGUAAAAGAAUAGACUGACAGUAUCAGACUAACAUCACAAUAUUCCCAACUGGUGGGAAAGCAACAGUCAGAAGAAUUAGAAAAUUUAAAUGAAACAUCACAGCAAAAUUUCACAAAAGUAAUAAAAAUGAGGCUGCAACCAAAAUGUUUACAAGUAGCCUAUUUGUUAGCCAAGCAAAGAAAACCAUUUACUAAUGCUGAAUUACAUCGUGCUUGAAGAUAGUAACCAACCCAAAGACAUGUGUCCAGAGAAAAUUAAGACAUCAGCCCUUUGAUGAGAACAGUAGUUUGAAGAAUGAGGAUUUUGGACACAACAUCAAAUGACACUGUUAAUUCUUUGCCUCUUACUAGUCAGUACUGCCUAGCUUUAUUUUUUGAGAAACCAUUGCUGGAUUUGAAGUGAUCGAAGAAUUUGUAUGGAACUACAAGUGGGAAUAUUUUCAAAAAAGUUGAUAAACAGUACAACCUGAAGUGGAAUCUACUAAGAUGUGAUGCAACCGAUGCUGGGAAAAAUGCAUGAAGCAGAAAAAAAGUUUAUUUGGUCAAAUUUUAAGGCUUGUGAAAACGUAAGUUGUUUAAAGCCUGUAGUUACUCACUUGAUUAUUCAUCAGCAGGUACUUCACAGGAAAUAUUGGUGUUACUGAACUGGUCAACAGUUAACUUCAUUUGCUCUUGUGGACUUAACCAUCUUCAGUUCCAUGAUUUUUUUUUUUUUGUGAGAAACAGAAGCUGAAUAUCCUGAUUUGAUUUGCCACACAGGCGUUCAAUGGCUUAGCAGUGCUAAAGAUUUAUUUUUAUUUUUUUGGGCUCUGGGCUGACAUUGAAAUUUUUCUGAAUGAGAAAAACCAUCCUCAACCACUGUUUUUUAACACUGAGUAACUUUGGAAAUUAACUUUUGCCACAGACUUGAAAAUGUUUCUUAAUGAAUUUGACCUGAAAUUACAAGGUACAACAACAUAAUAUGGUAAAUUCAUUUCAAUAAAAACUAAAACUUAAGAUUGUCAAGCUGCUUUAUAUACUUUCUGUGCUAUGAGAAGUCAAAACAGCGCUGUAUUGCCAAAUCCAUUUUUAGUGGAUAUAUUUUCCUGUAGCAGUUUUUUGGACCUUGAUGCAGUGCAAAGAAAAUUUUUAAAUUUUAAAAGCAUUUAACUGCAAUUAAAUGCUUUUAAAGUUUCCUCUUAAUCUUCUGUUGGAAAUGAAUCAUCUUGAAUGAAUGACAUGCUAAAGGGCAAAUACCAAAAAGAUGAAUCCUACAAAUGCCUUACAAGUGAUGAAUAUGCUUAACUAAAAUCACAUGCUCAUGGGUGGAUGUGUCAGUAUUUAGCAGUACCUUGACCUGUUUGUGUGAAAAGACAUUUUCAAAGAUGAAAUACGUGAAAUCCCAUUACACAUCAGCAUUAACAGAUUAACAUUUUCUAUUUAUUCCAAUGAGGGGAUACCAACUUUCAGCCCAAAUUGAGCAAAAUGUUACCUCCCGUCCCCUGCCAAAAAAUCCCAUUAUUCCCAUUAGUAGAACUCUAUUACUAAAAAAAGAAAAAAAAAUUGUACUCAAUAUUUUGAGUUUUCAAUUUUUAGAAUAAAAAUUUGGUGAAAAGUUUCCUUGAGUACCUAAAUAAUGUCCUUCAUUUUGUCUUAGCUUGCAAAGCCUCUAAUAUUUGCUACCUGCCCUUUUCAAAAAAAAAAAAAAAAAAAAAAAAAAGGCUUGUCCACCUCUCUACUAGAAGAAACUCAAGGGUCUAUGUCUGUCCUGUUUGCUAUUUCAUCUGCAUUGCCAAAUGCAGUGGCUCCUCUGGGUAGGCAACCUGAGGUGGAAUCAAAUUAUGAAUGCAUAUGUUAUCUCAUGUCUAUAAAAUAAAUGUGUUAGAAUUUAUAAAUAAAGGGAUAGGAAAAAUGCUGAUUAUUCUGUGUGUCGGUGCUUUGUAGUGAAGGCCAGUUCACACAUGCCAUUUGCUAUGUUGGUGUAAUUUAUAUGAGAGUUUCUUUUAUAACAACGUUACCUGUCAUUUAUUUUUCUAUUAAGACAUUAUAGAAACGUAGGACUGUACACAUCCAAAUCCUGCAGAAUUUUCAUUUCAGGUUUUGAAAGUUAAAAAAAUGUCACCAUAGAAUGAAAAUUCCAAGAAAACAAGAUUCAUGUACAUUAUCACUAGACAAUUUCCAUUUGUUUUAAACAGUUUUCUACAGCAUUAGUUACAUUUAACGUUUAGUAUAAAAGCAAUUGAGCAAUUUCUCUUUAGAAGUCCAUUUCAUUGCUUUGUAGCCAUAGUCUGUAGGUGAAUGAACAAGCUACAUUUCUCCAGAAUUACUCAUUUUCUUUUUAAAGAUAAACUGGUCAAUACUCUCCUUCCUGGUAUGGAGGAAUUUUUUGUAUAUGAGAAGCAUUCAUGAAUAUAAUCUGCCCUCUUGCUUUAUUGUCAUAGGAGGGGAAAUUCACUGCUUUCACACCCUUCUGUUUUGGCUCUUUCUCCCAAAAGAUAAGAAUCUUUAUUUAGUAUCAUACCAAGAAAUUGGAGUUCCUUUAGCUUCAGACUAUCAUCAUGGCUUCCAAAUUGUUAGGAAAUACAAGUUUGCAAGACCCCAAGGGGACUUAAUAUUUUACAUCUUACUAGCCAUGUCAUAGGUUUUAAGUGCUUUUAAUGGGGAACUGUUUCACUCAUGCCAUAUACCUGUUUUGUUUUUCUAAAAAAUUAAUACUGUAAGUUGUGAGCAGGUGUCUUGUAUCACUGCGAAACCCAUGCAUAAUAAAAACUUGUUCUUGAGCUA